AUCGUCGGCUCGGAGGCUGAGGGGCUGCCGCGGCCGGGAGCGCCCCUCGCCUCGCUCCUCGCUCCGCUUGGUGAGUUAGGGGGUCAAGAUGCGAGGAGGGCGGCGGAGUGGUGGGAGGGCCGAGGCGCGAACGGGCGGUGGGCCUCCCGCUCCCUCCGCGAUUCCCAGCCCCUGGUUACCCUGAGACUGCCCGGCUUCAGGGCCCUCAGCCCUGUCCAGCCCGCGCCCGCUCCUCUCCGACCCAGCCUUCCCCCUGCACCGCCGCUGUGGCCCCGUCCCCUCCGUCUGUCCAGCCCCCAGCCCGCGCCCGCAUCCCCUCACCAGCGGUCUUGCUUAAAUGCAGCUUCACUCGUGACCCCACUUUACCCCAGUUCCAACACCGAUCUCGGCCACGUCCCUUCGCCCCGCCCUGACACACCUCAUCCUCUCUCCCCACCCCUCUGGUAAUCCCGAUGCUCCGCGCUUACCUCCCCGAGACCCACCAUUCAGGUUUCCCCUUUUCUGGCUCAGCUUUCUUAUCCCAGUCACCCCCAUCCCCCGUCUAGCUCCCCAAGAUCUGCUCAUCCCAAACAUUCUACCUCCGCCCUCUCAUCUAAGACCCACCCCCAAAGUAGGUGCCCUGUUGAGCUCACCGCUUUCUUCUGGAUAACUCCGAUCUCAGCCUUAUUCCAAGUCUUAACUGUGUCUUCUCGUCCUUAGUCUCCUAGCCACUGUAUACCUUCCUUUGCGUCUCCUGCCGUACUGAGGACAGCCCAUCCCUAAGUCUUUGCCAAACUGUCCCGAACUCUUGCUGCCUCCUUUCCUACCACCCUCACCCAAUCUUGUUAAAAAUGACAUCUCCAUGUCCUUUCACCCCCGCUGACCCACCGCAACUCUUCACCCCAACUCUGCGUCCAUUGCUUCCCUCGACCCAACUCCCAUUCAACCUGAGAACUUAGUGCAGAGUCGCCUGCCAACUCCACCAGCUGCCCCUCAACAGCCAAAUGUAGGUGCUCACUCAGACCCGCAGUUACAGACUGAGCAGCAUGAUUGGCGGGUGCAGGGGCUCAGGUGGUAAAUAAGGGUGGAGGAGCAGUGGGCUCUCCCCAACUCUUGGGUGGGGCCGGGGUUUUUCCUGGCAUCUGGUCUCCUGCACCUGUCCUCAGGGAUUGUGUUUUUGGCAUUCAUAUUAAAUGACUUGUGCUGGCUGCUGGAAUGGUAGGUAUCAUUCAAAUAUCUGGAAGGUGAGAGACGGCCACUCACUCAGCUCACUUAGCACAGAAUGAUGGAAGCUGUCACUUCCUUCUGGUUGGUGUUCUCGCCCUGGAGAGCUUCUGGGAAGUUCUGUGUGGUGUUGGCUGUGGUCACAGAAUAUUGUUCGUGUUCCUUUUCUUGGCACUUGUAAGGGCCUCUCCCUGCCAGAGCUGAUGGCAGAUCAGUCCUGAUGCUGAAUUCAGGGGAUAUGAUGGGUGCCAGAGGCAACGUUACCUGUUGUGAAGAGUAUAGGUGUCAUGUGAUUCUCUGAGGGAGCAGCUGCGUGAGUGGAGAUGCUUUCAGUGGUGGAGAAUGGACUGGACCCCCAGGCUGCCAUCCCGGUCAUCAAGAAGAAGCUGGUGGGAUCCGUGAAGGCCUUGCAGAAGCAGUACGUGUCCCUGGACACGGUGGUCACUAGUGAAGACGGAGAUGCCAACACCAUGUGCAGCGCCCUGGAGGCCGUAUUUAUCCAUGGCCUGCACGCCAAGCACAUCCGAGCUGAGGCCGGAGGAAAAAGGAAGAAAAGUGCCCACCAGAAGCCUCUGCCCCAGCCUGUCUUCUGGCCCCUCCUGAAAGCUGUCACCCACAAACACAUCAUCUCAGAGUUGGAGCACCUGACGUUUGUCAACACGGAUGUGGGCCGCUGCCGGGCAUGGCUGCGGCUGGCCCUGAACGAUGGCCUGAUGGAGUGCUACCUGAAGCUGCUGCUGCAGGAGCAGGCCCGCUUGCAUGAGUACUACCAGCCCACCGCCCUGCUCCGGGAUGCUGAGGAGGGCGAGUUCCUCCUUAGCUUCCUGCAGGGCCUCACGUCCUUGUCCUUCGAACUCUCCUACAAGUCUGCCAUCUUAAAUGAGUGGACGCUCACCCCAUUGGCCCUGUCUGGGCUUUGCCCGCUUUCUGAGCUGGACCCUCUCUCUACCUCUGGUGCAGAACUACAGCGGAAGGAAUCUCUGGAUUCCAUUUCCCAUUCUUCAGGCUCUGAAGACAUCGAAGUCCAUCACUCGGGCCAUAAGAUACGGAGGAACCAGAAGCUGACUGCCUCCUCCCUCAGCCUGGACACGGCCAGUUCAUCCCAGCUGUCCUGCAGCCUAAACUCUGAUAGCUGCUUACUCCAAGAGAAUGGCUCCAAGAGUCCAGACCAUUGCGAGGAGCCCAUGUCCUGUGACUCAGACCUGGGCACAGCAAAUGCUGAGGACUCAGACCGGUCUCUGCAAGAGGUAUUGUUGGAAUUCAGCAAAGCCCAGGUAAACUCUGUGCCAACCAACGGACUGAGCCAAGAAACAGAGAUCCCCACACCACAGGCCUCGCUCUCCCUCCAUGGCCUCAACACCAGCACAUACCUGCACUGUGAGGCACCUGCAGAGCCCCUUCCUGCCCAGGCAGCCUCUGGAACUCAAGAUGGUGUCCACGUGCAGGAGCCGCGUCCCCAGGCGCCCAGCCCCCUGGACUUACAGCAGCCUGUAGAGAGCACCUCAGGCCAGCAGCCUUCUAGUACUGUCAGCGAGACAGCCAGAGAAGUGGGCCAAGGGAAUGGCCUGCAGAAGGCCCAGGCUCAUGACGGAGCUGGUCUGAAGCUGGUAGUUUCCUCACCCACCAGUCCGAAAAACAAGAGCUGGAUCUCAGAGGAUGACUUCUACCGGCCUUCCCGGGAGCAACCCCUGGAGAGUGCUUCAGACCACCCAAUAGCUUCUUACAGGGGGACUCCAGGGUCAAGGCCUGGUCUCCACAGGCAUUUUUCUCAAGAACCAAGAAAAAACUGCUCCCUGGGGGCGUUAGACCAAGCGUGUGUACCUUCCCCAGGAAGAAGGCAAGCCCAGGCAGCCCCAUCCCAGGGGCAUAAGAGCUUCCGGGUGGUACACCGGAGACAGAUGGGACUGUCCAACCCAUUCCGGGGUCUCAUGAAGCUGGGCACCGUGGAGCGGCGGGGGGCAAUGGGCAUCUGGAAGGAGCUCUUCUGCGAGCUCUCCCCGCUGGAGUUCCGCCUCUACCUGAGCAACGAGGAGCACACCUGUGUGGAGAACUGCUCGCUGCUUCGCUGUGAGUCUGUGGGGCCAGCCCAUAGUGAUGGGCGCUUUGAGCUGGUCUUCUCUGGCAAGAAGCUGGCCCUGCGCGCCUCCUCCCAGGACGAAGCUGAGGACUGGCUGGACCGGGUGCGGGAGGCCCUGCAGAAGGUCCGGCCUCAGCAGGAGGAUGAGUGGGUGAACGUGCAGUACCCAGACCAGCCUGAGGAACCCCCCGAGGCGCCCCAGGGCUGCCUCUCUCCCUCAGACCUGCUCUCGGAGCCCGCGGCCCUCCAGGGCACACAGUUUGACUGGUCGUCCGCCCAGGUUCCAGAGCCAGAUGCCAUCAAGGAGUCCCUGCUGUACUUGUACAUGGACAGGACCUGGAUGCCCUAUAUAUUUUCUCUGUCCUUGGAGGCUCUGAAAUGUUUCCGCAUCAGGAACAAUGAGAAGAUGCUGAGUGACAGCCACGGCGUGGAGACCAUCCGGGACAUCCUGCCAGACACCAGCCUUGGGGGCCCAUCCUUCUUCAAAAUCAUCACGGCCAAGGCUGUCCUGAAGCUGCAGGCCGGAAACGCCGAGGAAGCCGCCCUGUGGAGGGAUCUGGUCCGCAAAGUCCUGGCAUCCUACUUGGAGACAGCCGAGGAGGCGGUGACCCUGGGCGGGAGCCUGGAUGAAAACUGUCAGGAGGUGCUGAAAUUUGCCACCCGGGAGAAUGGCUUCCUGCUGCAGUACCUGGUGGCUAUCCCCAUGGAGAAAGGCCUUGACUCCCAAGGCUGCUUCUGCGCAGGCUGCUCCCGGCAGAUCGGCUUCUCCUUUGUACGACCCAAGCUCUGUGCCUUCUCUGGCCUCUAUUACUGUGACAUCUGCCACCAAGACGAUGCCUCAGUGAUUCCGGCCAGGAUCAUCCACAACUGGGACCUCACCAAGCGCCCGAUCUGCAGGCAGGCCCUGAAGUUUCUGACACAGAUCCGGGCCCAGCCCCUCAUCAACCUGCAGAUGGUGAACGCGUCUCUGUACGAGCAUGUGGAGCGGAUGCACCUCAUUGGGAGGAGACGGGAGCAGCUGAAGCUCCUGGGGGAUUACCUGGGCCUGUGCCGGAGUGGCGCCCUGAAGGAGCUCAGCAAGAGGCUCAACCACAGGAAUUAUCUCUUGGAAUCUCCGCAUAGGUUCAGUGUUGCUGACCUCCAACAGAUCGCAGACGGGGUGUAUGAAGGAUUCCUCAAGGCCCUGAUUGAAUUUGCCUCCCAGCAUGUCUACCACUGCGACCUGUGCACCCAGCGCGGCUUCAUCUGCCAGAUCUGCCAGCACCACGACAUCAUCUUCCCCUUUGAGUUUGACACCACAGUCAGGUGUGCCGAGUGCAAGACCGUCUUCCACCAGAGCUGCCAGGCUGUGGUGAAGAAGGGCUGCCCCCGCUGUGCCCGCCGGCGCAAGUACCAGGAACAGAACAUUUUCGCCUGAUGCCCAUCUGCUGACCCCGCUCUGAAAGCCGGGGGUGAGUGUGGCUCAGCCAUCCCGGCUGGGUUUGCCAUCAGCCCAGGAUACUCACCGUGUCACAGCUGUGUCCCCUUGUCAGGAAGACCCUCAGAUGUGGCCAGAGCACCGGCCUCCCAGAGAAAGCCCAGGAAGUCCCCGUGGUGUCCCCUGGCCCUCCCCCCACCCCUCUGCUGCAGGAGGCGUGGCCACCACCAGAUGCUCCCUGUCUGGGGCAGGCAGGGCCGUUUACUCACCAGGCCCUGGCUCACCAGCGUCCCGGCGCCUCCGUUAGGGCUGCCCAAACACUGUGGAAAGGGGACUUGGGGAGCAUUUUCAAUUCCACAUUCCUGAUUAAAAGGUCUAGUUUUUUAAGGUGGGUUUUUCCCAUUCAUAUUUCAACAGAAAGUAUUUUUUUAUUCUUGACCCUACGUGAGUCACCCAUGAAAUCCAGACAUUCUCACCCCCAGCGGAUGCACAGGAGCCACUCAGGCCUGGCUUAGAGGUAGCGGGUGGCUGGUGGGCAGGCCACUGCUGGGACAGGGUCUAUGGGCCCACCCAGUGCCUUUCCUUGGCCCUCACUGCCAGUGCCAAACCGCCCCUCAGCAGGGCAGGGCCAGUCCUGGCGACCCCGGUUCCUCUGUGUCCUCUUUACUCCCCACCCCAGUGCGUCUCGCCUGCUGAGCCCACCGCUUUCUCAGCGUCAGAGCCCCUAGCUCUUCUCUAGCCUGGGGCCUUGGCCCCAUUAGGAGAAGGAGAAAUGACUGGAAACCAGCACUGUCAGCACUUUGAGCCCUCCUCGGUUUAUGGAGGGUCGCCGUCUUGCCCACCCCCGAUCCCCGUGCGCUCCUCACCCCUCUACAGACAGGGGCGCUGCUGCAGAUGCUCCAGGCCCACCUUGGUGGGUGCCCGGGGUCACACUCUCUGCCUGACUGACCCCUGCCAGGGCACAGAUAGGCAGGACCCCAGAGAGGGCAGGCAGCCACGCCCUGCACUGUGGAGAAGUGACCUGGUCCUAAGCUGUGCAGGGCGUGCGGGGGAACUGCCCUGUGGAUGCAGCCACCACCUCACAAAGCCAUGAAUUCCCAAAGCAUCACUGAACUUGCCCAGCCGGGACACUGGAGACUGAAGAAGUUCCCCGGAGCAGGACUGCCUUUGAAGGGGCCUUGGGGCUGGGGUGGGAGUCUGGAAUUGUUUUCAAAGUGAUGGUCAGACCCUCCAGGCUUCGGGGAAAUGUGGGUUUGCUGGUCUCUCUGUCGCCUUCCCCCACCUCUCCUGGACCUAGCAGGCCCUCAGUCCUAGCUGUCUUACCUGCGCUCAGCUUGGAGUCAGGCCUCAGGUGGAGAGCCGCAUGUCACUGUCAGAGAUGAGCCCACCCCCACCCUUCCCUGGGGGCGAUUAGCUGCUGAGUCACCCACCCAGCCUUGGAGCUGGAUGCCUGUGCAGCAGAACAGAGGCAACGGUGGCAGGCAGGUGGAGGCUGCGCACAGCUUCUCCCGGUCAUGGCACACACCUGUGCCCAGACGCCAAUGCCUCCUAAGCCAGGAGCUGGGUUAUGCACCGCCAUGGCCCACAUUAACGCUCCACCACAAGCCCAGCCUAGUCAGAGCCCUCAUUGCCCCAUCCCUGAGUGGGCAGGAGCCUGGCCUGGGGAGGGCUUGGGCCUGUGAGGAUUCUCCCCGAAGGUGCCCUCGGAGGCAGCAGGUUUGAGGCCCUGGGGGGCCCGUUCCCCAGAAGCUGCCAGUGCUUUCAGAUGCAUUGACUCUUCCCGCCUCCCCUCCCUCAGAAAGGUAGUGCCCACACUAUUUUUAAAAUGUUAUUUUAUGCAAUACACUGUUCCUAGUGAGCAGGGCUCUGGCCCUGAGGAGUCUUUGCAAUGUAUUGAAGGAAUUGCUGCCGUGUGAGUUUUGAAUGAUUUUGCAGUAAAGACCUGAUCUUUCUCAUCA